AAAAAUUAAAAAAGGAUGUGAAAAGAUGCUACUCGCUUUUGGCCUCCCGGAGAUGGCGCUAUGAGGGUGACGGAGUUAAUUAGUGCCUCCAAACGCCGUGUGUGAGCUCAUCGAAGUCAUGCUCUGCACACAUAUUAUUUAUAGCAGAUCUGAGGCAUGCAUGGUGUUUGACAUUUCUGUCUUUUAAGUAGGGGGACUUCAAAAAGUCGUGGGCAUCCCCCUAGGCAAAGUGCAGUGGGCAGGGACCAGGCAGGGUGCGGGCGCAAGGCGAACGCGCAGACCACGAGUGUCCUGGCGCAGGUGCCGGGGGCGGCGGCUGCAACUCCGCAGCGUCCGCUCGGGAGGAGAGUUCGCGGCUGAUCUCCGGAUGCCUUGCAGAUGCAAAAUGUGUCUCUGGCCAGCAGGAGGAAGGAAGAGGAAGUGAGAGCAGCGGCAGCCGGCGGUGCAGCAGCCGGCCGACCCAGAGUGUAUAGACACGUGUGGCCGUUUACGCUGUAGGAUCCUCAUUCCCACUGGCUUUGAACAUUUUGGGGACUUACAAUGCCGCCACCCGCGGACAUCGUCAAGGUGGCCAUAGAAUGGCCGGGCGCCUACCCCAAACUCAUGGAAAUUGAUCAGAAAAAACCACUGUCUGCAAUAAUAAAGGAAGUCUGUGAUGGGUGGUCUCUUGCCAACCAUGAAUAUUUUGCACUCCAGCAUGCCGAUAGUUCAAACUUCUAUAUCACAGAAAAGAACCGCAAUGAGAUAAAAAAUGGCACUAUCCUUCGAUUAACCACAUCUCCAGCUCAGAACGCCCAGCAGCUCCAUGAACGAAUCCAGUCCUCGAGUAUGGAUGCCAAGCUGGAAGCCCUGAAGGACUUGGCCAGCCUCUCCCGGGAUGUCACGUUUGCCCAGGAGUUUAUAAACCUGGACGGUAUCUCUCUCCUCACGCAGAUGGUGGAGAGCGGCACUGAGCGAUACCAGAAAUUGCAGAAGAUCAUGAAGCCUUGCUUUGGAGACAUGCUGUCCUUCACCCUGACGGCCUUCGUUGAGCUGAUGGACCAUGGCAUAGUGUCCUGGGAUACAUUUUCGGUGGCGUUCAUUAAGAAGAUAGCAAGUUUUGUGAACAAGUCAGCCAUAGACAUCUCGAUCCUGCAGCGGUCCUUGGCCAUUUUGGAGUCGAUGGUGCUCAAUAGCCAUGACCUCUACCAGAAAGUGGCGCAGGAGAUCACCAUCGGCCAGCUCAUUCCACACCUGCAAGGGUCAGAUCAAGAAAUCCAAACCUAUACUAUUGCAGUGAUUAAUGCGCUUUUCCUGAAGGCUCCUGAUGAGAGGAGGCAGGAGAUGGCGAAUAUUUUGGCUCAGAAGCAACUGCGUUCCAUCAUUUUAACACAUGUCAUCCGAGCCCAGCGGGCCAUCAACAAUGAGAUGGCGCACCAGCUGUAUGUUCUACAAGUGCUCACCUUUAACCUCCUGGAAGACAGGAUGAUGACCAAAAUGGACCCCCAGGACCAGGCUCAGAGGGACAUCAUAUUUGAACUUCGAAGAAUUGCUUUUGAUGCUGAGUCUGAACCUAACAACAGCAGUGGCAGCAUGGAGAAACGCAAGUCCAUGUACACGCGAGAUUAUAAGAAGCUUGGGUUCAUUAAUCAUGUCAACCCUGCCAUGGACUUCACGCAGACUCCACCUGGGAUGUUGGCUCUGGACAACAUGCUGUACUUUGCCAAGCACCACCAAGAUGCCUACAUCCGGAUUGUGCUUGAGAACAGUAGUCGAGAAGACAAGCAUGAAUGUCCCUUUGGCCGCAGUAGUAUAGAGCUGACCAAGAUGCUAUGUGAGAUCUUGAAAGUGGGCGAGUUGCCUAGUGAGACCUGCAACGACUUCCACCCGAUGUUCUUCACCCACGACAGAUCCUUUGAGGAGUUUUUCUGCAUCUGUAUCCAGCUCCUGAACAAGACAUGGAAGGAAAUGAGGGCAACUUCUGAAGACUUCAACAAGGUAAUGUGGAUCUCGGAUAGAGGCAGGGGAUUCCCGCAGCGCUAAAGGGGCCUGCUGCAUGGUCCCUUGGCUGUGUGCAGAAGGCAAUUGGCAAGGUGGGGAAAUGAGGAAGAUUGCAAUGAUAGUUGCUUCAAGAAUGGAGAAAGACAAACAUCCCUGUGUAGACAUGAAUCUGUGUGCUGGGGAUGACCUCAUCCCUCUGGGGGUACGCUUGGAGCAGCUUUGUUCCUUUGUCUAAGUUGGAGCCACCAGCAGAGAGUUUUUCUUGGGACACGUUAUCAAGGCGAAUGUUUUCUUUCAUAGCAUUAGUUUGGGAUGCCUUGUCAAUAUUGCAAGAUCUGUCGGGGAAGGGGCCUUCCCUCCACCUGUCCAGGAGAUUGGUACAGAGCAAAUGAGAUCAGGAAUACUGCUCCACCUAGUCCGGUGGUUUCUUUGUGGAUUAUGGAUGUGUUGUGAUCAUCUGCCCCGAGCUACGUCAAGAAGAAUUUUUAUUAAAAUGAAAGAUCCCUUUCCAAGAACUGAGUCAUUAAGGUUAUAUGCAACAUUUCUUGGUUUACAGUAAGCAUUUGAUCCUUUGAACUGAGAUGUCCUUUAGUUUUCUAUAUCAUAAUGUCUCACAAGAGUGUGACUUUCACAUUUCCAUUUGUGUGUGAAUAACCAGCAGAGGGAAGAGCAUUGGCCAACUUAGAGCAGAAGCACUAUCCAUGCUUUCAUAGAGAAGCAAAAUCUUUGUCCUUAGAUAAAGGCCUGAUUAGCAAUAAUAACUAUUGCAGCCUUUAGUACUUUUAAUUUGCUGCUAUAUACAGCUGUGACUGUGGUCAGGCCCAUCACCCAUGACCACUCUCACCCAGCACUAAGGGCUGUGACUGUAAGAGUCGAAGGGUCUGGCCCUCAGUCAUACUGUGGGGCUUUCAUGGGCGUGCUUGGUGCAUAACAUAAUCUCUGAAUUUCACCUGCACUUAAUAUACUUGUUGGUCAUUGCCUCCCUGUCACCUUCUCCCUGGAUAUACAUCUCAUCCUUGUUUCCCACUAUAUUUCUCAUUUGUGGCAUCUUGAACCAACACCAAUUGAAAAGAAAGAAAAUCAGGAAAAGGACCUAAGCUUCAGUCAGGUCCUAACCUGAGUUUCUUCCUCAGCACAGUGAUCUCACUUGCCAUAUCAUCUCUGUCAUCCCAACGAUCUGUCCUUUGCAUCUUGGUCAUCGAUUGAAUUCCUUGAAAUAGACCCCAGUAAUGCCCUUCUGUGGAGAGCACUGGUCUGGAAGCUGCAAUCCAGAGCUGUCAUGUGUCUGAGCAGCUAUGCCGGAGGACAGGCUUGAUUCAAGAAGGGAAGUGGAGAAAAGAAGCCCAUUAAUUUCCUUAGGAUUAUAACUGCAGCCUCCUAAGUGUACUUCGCUUGAUUGUGAGAGACUUUGCAUUUCAGGUGCAAAUCAUCCCUGGGAAAGAGGGAAGGAGGAGCAGGGAGGCCUUUGUUCAAUCAAACCAAAAAAGAGAAUUAAAUCAGUAGUCUUUGAAAUUGGCUAAGGGACUAAGGCCACUUUGCCCUGGAUCAUUUCAGCUCUUUCAUGUGCUGCUGUGUGAAAGCCAUCCAGUCCUCAGCUUUGCGAGCUGGGGACACCUGUUCCUCCAGGAGAAGGAGACCUCACCAGUUGUUACGGAUUUGGGCAUCAGAUGUCUGCUUUCUGAGAGAUCUCAUUUAUCCUGCUUUUCCUAAAUUAUAAAUUCUGCAUUUUGCAGAAUAAUAUCUGCAAAUAAUAAUGUUUCAGAUAUUAUUGUUGUUGAUCUAGGCACAGAUAAGCUGUGUAGAAAAUAUUAUGAAAGUUCUGCAGAGGACUGACUCUGGGGAUGAGCAUUCAGACACUUAAAUCCUAUAGAAGUUACAUUUUGUAACAUGAAGCACCAAGAGUUCCUUGUUAGCAAAGGAAGCCGGAGGCCCCAGGAUGGAGGAGGUGGGCACAGCUGGUGGAGGGAGGUGACCAUAGCUCUAGGGUCCCUGUGGCUUAUCAUGGCCAUGUGCUCAGAUUGGUGGCAGACAUCCUGCCUGUUCAGGGCCCUGCCAGGUGACAGCAAGCCCCCCAGAGUGUCACUGUGAAACUUUUAUCAUAAUUAGCCUAUAUGGCUGUGAAAUCUCUUCAGCAAGACCUAAGAGCCAGGUUUUGGGUGCAGUUUCUUACCGUAGCUCUAAUGCCAUUUUUUGCAUUGUUUACAGAUCAUAGACUAAUGCUGGGGGUCACACCUCUAUUGCCAAGUAGGGAUGACAGUUUAUGGCUCAGGACAGGCAGCUCCAGGCCUGAGGGCCAGAGGUUCCUGCCUCACAUCCAAAUAGCCAUCAGGCAAGAGCAGAUAUCAGAGGAAAAUCCAGGAUGGGAAGGACAAGGAAUUUUAAUUUUCUACAUUAAAUACUUUCAUCGUGUUUGCUUUUUUUCUCUUUUUUUCAGUACUAUGCAUGCCUUACUUAUGUAACCAGAAAAAUAUAUCAGGUAUUUACAUUUUUGUCAUGCGUAUAUAACUUUUCUGUUGCUGAUACAACAAAUUACCACAAAUUUAGUAGCUUAGACAAUGCAAAUUUAUCUUACAGUUCAUAGUUCAGAAGCCAGCAAUGGAUUUCACUAGGACAAAAUCAAGGCGGCAGCAGAGCUGUGUUUCUUUCCAGAGGCUCUAGGAGAGAAUUUGUUUCCUUGCCUUUUUCACUUUCUGGUGGUCACCUGCAUUCCUUGGCUUAUGUCCUUCUUGUCCAUCUUCAAAGCCAGCAAAGACAGCUUGAGUCCUUCUCAGAUGCCAUCCCAUCACCCUGAUCCCUCUUCUGCCUUGGUCUUCCACCUUUAAGGACCUUGUGAUUACAUUGGGUGACCUGGAUAAUCCAGCAUCAUCUUCCCAUCUUAAAGUUGGCUGAUAAUAACCUUAAUUCUGUCUGCAACCCCAAUUCCCCUGUGCUGCAGAAGGUAACGUAUUCUCAGGUUCUGAGGAUUGGAAUGCAGGCACCAAUGGGAAGCUGUUAUUCUGCCUAUUUCCAGUGUGUAUUUGAUUUGCAGCUAUAUUAGGUUUUUAGAUGUGUAGAUCAGUUUAAAUUAAUGAAACACGGACAGAGGAGCCUUUUGUUUGCUUUUCUUUUUGCUGGUAGACAUGAUACCUGUCACAGAGUUCUGCUAGUGACAGCUCAGAUGCAGAUAUAAUUAUGUCCCUUUUCUUUUAUGGCCCUGUUCCGCCUCCACUAGCCUUUUUAAAAAGGAAGCCUCUUUGUGACAGCUUCUGGUUCAUUUUGAAGACUGCCUUUCUGAUUUUUUUCUGCUGCCCAUCUAUCAGCCACUGUUCUGCUUUACUUGAUAAUAAGUUGGAGAAGAGAGAAGAGCUGAAAGUUAAAUCAGUUCACUUUUCUUCUUGUUAUUAACUUGGUAGCAGAGGAGAUUGAAUUUAGGAACAAAUGUGAGUUGUGAGUUACUGAUAGAUUUAAUGUUUUUUUCUUAUUCUCUGACUGUCCAAAUUCAAAUUCAGAAAUGUCUUUAAAAAAGCCCAACAUGAAACAUAAUUUCUUUUCAACUUUCUUGGACACUAUCUCAGGUUCUUGCCACUGUAAACAGAGCAUGGAAGGUGGGUUUAUUUGUCAACCCUGAGACCCAGGGCUCUGUGAGCAGGGCUUAGCUAUCUGUCUUCUUUAGCUCCUCACUGGAGAAGGAGUGCCCCUCAAUUUAAAAUUUUGAUUUGCCCAACAAACUAUGCUGGAUUCUAUCAGAGGCAGGAAUAGCUUCUGCAGCCCGCCUUCCUUGGGACACCAGUUUAUAGAUAUCUAGUGCUUGGUAGUUAAUGCCACUGCUGGAAGAGGGUGUUUGGAAAAGCAGCUGUCGUCUGCUCUUCCGGGCUUGGGAAGCAGCAGAUGGAAUGUUUUUUAUUUAUAUAAGAGAAGUAGAAUUGAAGAGUGAUUAAAAUAUUUAUGCUUUGAAAAGUACUUUCUUUCAGUUUCUCAAUAUAGCACUCUGCAGAAUAAUCCAUUGAUUCAGGCCAUUGAGUGUGUGUUCUAUCAUUACCAAUAUUUUAGAGCAUGCAUUAUUCAUUUUUAUGGGCAUUAGAGAAGAGCUAAACUGCAGCUGGAUACCUCAGCACACAAGUAGCCCCAUAAUCAUUUCAUUGAAAUCCUCAUUUUUGAGCGGGAUAAGAAAGGGGACACAAGUAACUUGGAUAUUUUAGGUAUGGGAAUCUCAUUUAAAGCAUGUGUGGCUAACUACUCCACUGUAAAAAAAAAAUGUAAUGAGAGUAUACACUUUAGAGUAUAUGUCUGUGUGUAGCAGUGUUUCUCAGCUUUAGCUGUACGUCAGAAUCACCUGGGGGCUUUUGAAAACCCUGUUAUCCCACCGGCCAACCGCACCACAGAUUAAUUAAAUCAUCGGGGGUGGCGGGGGAAGCUAUGAAUGAGUAUUUUCAUUAAGGUAGAUUUGAUCAUUAAAGGUGAUUUAUGUUAAUAGAAUCGCCAUCAUUAACACAUGUGAUACUUAUCACAAGCUACUGUAAAUUUCGUGCAUUGAUGGAGUAGGAUGCUUGUUGACCUGUGUGACCCAGGUUUUCAUCCUGGAUCUGCUAUUCCAGAGCUCUAUGUCUGAGAAUCUAAAAAUAAUAAUAGUUUUUAAAAGGAUACAUCACCCUGUCUUUUGGUGGGGUGAUAAUAAAUUGAAGUAAUUACUGUAAAAAUGCUCUGAGGAAGUAAAAAUGGUAUAUGUAGUUGUGGAGUGUUCUUUUGUACUGAAUAAGAUAAAGCCUGUCUAUGAAAAAUGAGUAAAUUGCCCUUUUCACAAACAGACAUUUUUUGGCUAUGUUAAAAAAAAAAAGUGAAGCUAUGAAUUUCACAGUAAAUUCUGAACUGAAUUAGUAACCCAUGUAACUUUGACAAAAAUAGGCUUUAAGCUGAAAUUUUCAUGGAUUUUGGAAGUGUCUUCCUCCAAACAACUUUAUUAGGUACCUUAGUUUCCCGUGUGAAACACACGGUAGCAACCUAAAAAACAGCAGGUCCCAUGAUUUUCACAUAUUUAAUGGCUGGUGAGAAUUAAGUCCUCCCCAACAAUUACUAGUUGCCCAGAUCUCUUCGCUGAUGAUUGACGCUUUUAUAAACCAUCAAAAUAUUUGUUCCUAGCAUUGGCGUUACUUUAGACGCUAUCAAAAUUGACAUUAUAAGCCAAGAUCAGAUGAUUGUGCCAUACUUUCAGAUUACCAAAAUGGAAGAAACUAAUUUGAAAAAUGAAGUCACUCUAGAGUAAAAGCACUAUCUUGAAACUUUAUCUAGCAGCAUAAUAAACUAAGCGCACACAAUAGAGCUUAGAAUCUCAGGCUUGCAAAUGAAAAACCAUCCCUUAAAAUAGCAGAGACUGUGCACAGGGAGAACCCAGGCCCAUUAAACAAAGCUGCAGCUGCCCCUGGCCAGGCUGUGAGCUUCAACCGAGUCAAUGGGAGAAAAUCUCAAUUAGGAAGAACGGGAGAGCAGGACAGAAGGAAACAUCCUGAGAAAUCUCCUAUGAAGAUUAUUCAUAGGAAAUAACCACCAGCUAGUCACAUCUAGUGGAUUAUAGUGUGGGAUAGAAAAGGGAUUGUGUUUAAAACCUUAAAGGCAGCUAACACAUGAAUAAAAAAGGGAAAUGUGUUUGCUUCUCAAACUGUUUGCAGCUUACUGACUUUCUGUGCAUGCUUUUCAGGGGACAAUUAUAUAUUCAGGAGUCUCCUUACUAGGGCAGUUCAACUUCAUAGUGGUGCAGACGGCGCUCUGUUGGUUAGCUGAGCUGGCCUAGGGAAUGAAAGGUGGUCUGUAAGUCUCAUCAUGAAUAAACAUGAGUCUCCUCAUUUGCGUGAGGCAGGUGACUGUAAAAUAUCUUGGAGCAAGCUGUGAAAGGAAGCUUUGUGCAUCCAUGCCCAGGGGAAGCUGGGAGGACUCAGCGUUGUUUAUCUUCAUUAGAAUUCCAUCUAGUGCUGCUGUUAUUGAUCUGAACUGGGCCUGGUGUGGCUAAUAAAGUAGGUGUAUGUUUUAAUUGAAACAUGAAUAUUUGAGUAGAGGAGAAGUCUUUUAAAGAGCCCUAAUGUCCUACACUGAGC